UUAUCAUUGGAAUCAGUGGGCUCUACAAGAAACAUGGUGGUGAUAUGUGCUUCUGAUGAGGGCCUCAGGAAGCUUACAGUCAUGGUGGAAGAUGAAGGGGAUCCAGCAUGUCACAUGGCGGAAGAAGGAGCAAGAGAGAGUGAGAGGGAGGUUUCAGACUUUUUAAACAACCAGCUCUCACGUGAACCAACAGAGCAAAAACUCACUCAUUACCAUGGGGAUGGCACCAAACCCUUCAUGAGCGAUCUGCCCUCAUGAGCCAAACACCUGCCAGCAGGCCCCACCUCCAGCUUGGGGAUCACAUUUCUUUUUUGAGACAGAGUCUUGCUCGCCCAGGCUGGAGUGCAGUGGUGCAAUCUCGGCUCACUGCAGCCUCCGCCUCCUGGGUUCAAGCGAUUCUCCUGCCUCAGCCUCCCAAGUUGCUGGGACUACAGGCAUGCACCACCACGCCCAGCUAAUUUUUGUAUUUUUAAUAGAGGUGGGGUUUCACCAUGUUGACCAGGCUGGUCUUGAACUCCUGACCUCAGGUGAUCCACCCACCUCGACCUCCCAAAGUACUGGGAUUACAGGUGUGAGUCACCGUACCCGGCCAGGGAUCACAUUUCAAUAUGAGAUCUGGAGGGGACAAACAUCCAAACUCAGUCACUGGGGAAAGAGAUGAUAACCUUCAUGGGAUUCUCUCAGAGUCCCACAACAUAAAAAAGUUUAAAUCCAUCCUGGCAUUAGACUUUCCCAUCUCCAUUACUUAACAUGGACUAGUUUUAUUAGUAUACAACUUCUCAAUCCUUAGUUUCCUCAACUGGAAAAUUGGAAUAUUAACAUCUACCUGUUGCAGAAUGUAUUCUCCACGUGUUUGAGUAAUUACAGACAGCCUUUUAACUUCUCCCCAGCCCACUGUUAUGUCCAAAUACAAUGAGCCCUCUUGUUACCUGGCACAUAAAAAAUAAAUGGGCCAGGAGUUGUGCAUUUAUUUGGGUGUUGUGAGCAAAGAAGGGAGUGGCACCAAGUAGUCACCCUUUUUCCUUCCUCAGAUCCUAGGACAGAAUGCAUGCUGGGCACGCUUCUCCUCAGGUUGGGUAGCACACGCAAGCUACACGUGGUGGUUGUGGGCGUGCCAUAGGAAAAUGUUCCUAUUCCUUUCCCACAUGUUUUGGGUGGCCUUCCUAUUCCUUUACCCCAUCCUAUUCCCCCAUUCCUAUCCCUUUCCCCCAUCCUAUUCCCUUCCCCAAGGAAGGUUCCUAUUCCUUUCCGCCAUGUUUUGGGUGGCCUGAGCUGUCACCUGACCAGGAUGUCUGCAGUCUGAGUGUGGAUCUUAGGUGCAGGCUUGUUUAAAUACUUUUUCUCCCCUCUCCUCUCCAUAUCUCAGACUGUCUUCUAGCCGAUCUGUCUCCUCCAAGGCUUGUGCAAAAAUGGGGUGUGUAUUUCUCAUUAGCUUUAGCUAAGUCAGUGAGAAAGGAUCUAAUUACUACUGUUGGUUUGACUGCGUGAUCUUAACAGAGAUAAGUCUAAAAAAUGACAGAUUUUUCUAGCCAGAUUGUUCAUAUUGUAAUAAAGUCACCCCUGUUCACUAUCUCAUUUAAACCAAAACUUAAUACCUAAACUAUGGACAUUUGGUAUGGUUUACAGACAUUUUUGUUAAAGAAGGGGAAAAGUCAUAAUAUGUUCUUGAUACAUAGGGUAGCACCCACUCACUUUUCAUCGUUUUCAAAGAGAUGGCCCAUAUCCUACCCAAUUGUAUAUCGUAAGGUUACAUGAGAAAUCUUGUGAAUCAGGUUCCUUCUACCUUGAGGUAUAAGGUAGUAAUUGAGUUAUAUACAAGCCAUUUUGAUGAAUGGAUAUUAGUUCAUUUUCCCUUUUCUAGAUUAUAAGUAUUUGUGGAUUGAUCUCAUCUGGGAUUAAGCAAAGUUUCUUACAAAUAGAUGUGUAGUCAGGAGGUUUUUGUGCUGUGAACAUUUUGGUGGUAUGGUGAAAUCUUGACCUCAGAGUAAUAGUUUUAAGUGUACAAAAUAAAAUGCAGGAAUACAAAAGAAAUUGGUUAUAUUGAAAUAUAGUUAUAAAAAUAUUUUUAAAAACAAAUUUGUGAUAUUGUGAUAUAUACUCUUCUAUGUUAAUAUAUUAAAUAACAAUAGCCAGAAGUGGGUCUAAACAAUGCCAUAAAUCAGAAACAAUAAUGAACAUCGAUGAUACUUCAAGAUAUCCACCCCAACUGCAACAUAAUAUGAAAACAUCUGUGAUUUCUCUUGGUGAAUGUCAGAGUUCACAGAUGCCCUGACUUAUGUUCACAGACAUGAGCCCCAGGUUAAAACACGCUUUCAAUAAAUGACUGAAUCGAGAAGUGCCUCCCUCCCGUGUGAUCUCCUCGAUGCUGCAAAACUAGAUCUAAAGAGGAGUAACUCAGUGCCCCUUCUCCUGGACUUCACAGUCCGGUCAGAAGAGACAAAUAACUGGCCUGUUGUGAUAAGCUACAGCAGACCUCCCAGCUGGCCCCCAGGUGGAGAGAGAUGGGGAAAAGGAGGCAUCGCAGAGGAAAUGUGAUUUCAUGUGUGACAAACAGUGGCAAAACAACACUGGCUAAGAAUUUGCAGAAACACCUCCCAAAUUGCAGUGUCAUAUCUCAGGAUGAUUUCUUCAAGCCAGAGUCUGAGAUAGAGACAGAUAAAAAUGGAUUUUUGCAGUACGAUGUGCUUGAAGCACUUAACAUGGAAAAAAUGAUGUCAGCCAUUUCCUGCUGGAUGGAAAGCGCAAGACACUCUGUGGUAUCAACAGACCAGGAAAGUGCUGAGGAAAUUCCCAUUUUAAUCAUCGAAGGUUUUCUUCUUUUUAAUUAUAAGCCCCUUGACACUAUAUGGAAUAGAAGCUAUUUCCUGACUAUUCCAUAUGAAGAAUGUAAAAGGAGGAGGAGUACAAGGGUCUAUCAGCCUCCAGACUCUCCGGGAUACUUUGAUGGCCAUGUGUGGCCCAUGUAUCUAAAGUACAGACAAGAAAUGCAGGACAUCACAUGGGAAGUUGUGUACCUGGAUGGAACAAAAUCUGAAGAGGACCUCUUUUUGCAAGUAUAUGAAGAUCUAAUACAAGAACUAGCAAAGCAAAAGUGUUUGCAAGUGACAGCAUAAAGACGGAACACAACAAAUCCUUCCUGAAGUGAAUUAGGAAACUCCAAGGAGUAAUUUAAGAACCUUCACCAAGAUACAAUGUAUACUGUGGUACAAUGACAGCCAUUGUUUCAUAUGUUUGAUUUUUAUUGCACAUGGUUUUCCCAACAUGUGGAACAAUAAAUAUCCAUGCCAAUGGACAGGACUGUACCUUAGCAAGUUGCUCCCUCUCCAGGGAGCGCAUAGAUACAGCAGAGCUCACAGUGAGUCAGAAAGUCUCCACUUUCUGAACAUAGCUCUAUAACAAUGAUUGUCAAACUUUUCUAACUGGAGCUCAGAGUAAGAAAUAAAGAUUACAUCACAAUCCAAUAUCUGUGGAAUUCAUUGUGUAUGUUUAUGUAUUUGUGUGUAGGUGUGUAUGUGUGUGUGUGAUACAUACAUACAUCAAGUAUCACAAGACAUUGACCUUAUAUAUUAUGCACUGUGAUGUUUUUCCGUCUUUAAUUAUAAAAAACAUAUUGAUCACAACCACAAUUUGGAAAAUGUUGCUCCAUACCAUCCCAUACCAACACUCACCACCUGCAAAUAAUAGCAUUACUAGGAGCUGCAGUCACAAUGAAUAAAUCAACAAUUCGCUACAAGAUCUAGGAUUAUUUGUGUAUUUUGUUGAGUGUGUGUGUGUGUGUGUGUGUGUGUGUGUGUGUGUGUUGGCGUGUAUCUAAUACCAUUGUAUCUCAUUGUUGAGACUUUGUUACAAAUAGGGUUUCUGGUUUCUUUCUCCCCCCUCGUGGUUCAUUUUGUUUUUGUCAAACCAGUGGUCUAAAAUCACAGAAAUAAGCAAUUACUUCAAUCAUGUGGAAUCCAGGGGACCUAUCUUUGGAAAGCACAGAAGGAGAUCUGAAUUGUGUGAUCUCUUGAGGCUGCUUUCAAUGCUGGAAUUUAAAUUAUGUACUGAACAAUCUUUUGCUUAUUAAUAAAAAGAUUACACACAA